AGUAGGAACGCCGAGUCGGCUGCCGUGGCUGUGCUGAGGGUGGCGGCCGGAUAGGUGCGGAGCUUCCUGAACGAGGCAGGAGGGGUGCGAGGUUCAGGGGCAGGGCCCGGGCAGCCGAAGUCGUUAGGGAGGCGGUGACCUGACGGUGGGCGGCGGACAUCUCGCGGCAGGGUCGAGGGCUGUGAAAGCGGUUUAGUGAUUGAAGCGCUACGUUUGUGUGAGGAAUUCUUGUCGUUGUCAGCGCCUGAGAACUUAGUUGGGAGCGGACGUUUACGUCGAAUCUCUCGUUUGGGACCCCAUUCUUGAAUGUGGGAAGAAGUGAGAGCGCAUGUUUGCUCAUCUAGAGACAGCCGUAUUAAUAACGAUAGGAUACAAACCAUCACCCCACCAAGUGAUAGCAGCUGUUAACCUGUGGGCGGUUACGUGCCGGUCACUGUUCCAAGCCCCUCACAUAUCGCGUCACUGAAUCUUUAUAGGGACCCAGAACUCCAUUUGACAGAUGAGGAAACGGAGAGGCAGACAGGUGACCUGACUUCCCCACAAUCGCUGCAGGACAGGAAGAAAGUAAACUCCAGAGCCCGUGCUCUUAGCUACUAAGCUGUACUGCUCUUCAUUUUGGUAAAUGGGGCGGGUGGAGUGUAUAUAUACGUAAUAUAUAUGUGUGUGUGUAAGCGUAUGCGUUUUUAUUUCUUAAAAAUAUGGCUCAGCCGUAUUUAUUUACAGUUAUUGGAAUCUUUCUCCUCCAACUGAGAAAAUAACUGGAGGAGAAACUACAAUUAUUUCUACACGCUUACUACACAAUGCCUGGAAGACUUACAAAAACACUAAAUAGUGCAGUUCCACGUACUUGGUGUUUAUUCCUUUUUUUUUUUUAACCUUUCUCCUAGAUUAUGAAUGAGUUGAGGAAAGAGAUGGUACAGUCAUUCUAAUAACGAUAGUAAUGAUAAUAUAAACAACCAUCACCAUAAAAAAUUCUCUUCUGGCUUAGCUCAAAUAUCUGGCACAAAUGAAAGAAUAGAGAUAACCAGUGUUUAAUAUUUUAGUAAAGGGACUGUUUUGGCAGGGCAUGGUGGCUCACGCCUGUAAUUUUAGCACUUUGGGAGGCUGAGGCAGGGGAAGAUUGCUUGAGGCCAGGCCUAGGGUUCAAGACCAACCUGGCCAACAUAGCGAGACCCUGUCUUUAAAAAUAUAUUUUGGAGUAUGUCCUUCCAGUCUUUCAUGGAAUUAUAUGAAUUUAUGUAAUAUGUAUAUUAUAUAUUCUACAUAUAGUAUACUGUAUAUAUUUAUGAUGAUGAUAAUGAUGCGUUGCAACCUGGAGAGAGCAUAAGGAAAAGAUAGGAAACAUUUAUUCAUAUACACAAAACAUUAAUUGAACUUUGUGCAAAAACUGUCUCGUCUUUCCUAUUAGAUAGGCCCUUGGAGUGAAUGGCUUACAUUAGUUCUCUAUCUCCACAGGUACUGUGGUACUACUUGGUACGUAGUAGGUACUCAAAAAAUGUUUGCGAGUGAAUGAAUGGCUACUUCUAAGUUGGUUUGUAUGUCAGUGAGUAGUUGUAUCUGGAUUUUUUCUCUAUGUGUUUUGGAAAUGUGUAAUGUGUUUAUAUUAUAUGCCCAUAUAUUCUGAACUCCAUAGUGUUGUCUUAAUCUACCUUUCUAGCUUCAUGCCUUCCCAUUGUUCUUCUCUCUGCCAUGGUAACUACUCCCUACUGUAACUGUCCAUGUUCCAUACUGUCAGACCUCAGGCCUUUGGCUGUACCCUCAUGUUAUUUCCAUAUCCUUGAAUCCUGUCAUUGGCAUCAUCAUCUGUCAAAAUCAUAAGCUUCUUUUAAGGCAGGUGUUGCCAACUCAGAUGCCUACAGAGGUUAAUCAGGUAGCAUAAUUUGAGUGAAGUGGAUUUGCGUGGGGGAUUGUAGGGAGCUGGAGAGCAACUGCCCUAGCUAAAAGGGCCCAGCGGCUAUUUAGCACAAGCUAGUUAUUACAGAGUUGAAUGUGGGCCCGGUGUUGCUAGAUCUUUUAAUUUUACAAGUUAGAAGUUGGAAGCCUAUAUUUUUAUAUGAAGUCUGAUUUUUAAAUGUUGGCAUCUAGUUUUUGCAAAGGUUAAAUACUGUGCAGGCCAAAUAAAAACAUCUGUAGGCUGGAUUUGGCACUUAAAUUCCCAGUUUGUGACCACUACUCUAGGCUUAUUUCAGGUACUUUGUUCAUGAAUUACGUUGUCUGAUUCUAAUGGAGUUCUGUUUUUUUUCAGCAUUUUGUGUGUUGGAUGGUCUGGCAGGGAUGUUUCAGCAUUUUGUGUGUUGGACUGAAUGCAGCACCUGUUAUAGUGCUGCAUCCAGUCUGCCUUAGUUUUAAUAUGCCUUUCUUUUCUAAUACAUUAGAAACAUUUUGAUAGCAUGGGUUGGGUCUAAUUCUGCACUUAGUACAUAUCAGUACAUACCUACAGCGUGUGUGUACAUAUGUGUGAGAUGUAUUGAUUUCUACUCUGAUAAUCCUUGGUUAUCCUGGAAACUAGUGUCUGUUCUUUGUAGAGACACCAAUAGUAUCUUGGCUUUAAUUGCCAAAGAGCUCUACAUCUGGAAGGAAUUGAAUUGAGUAACACUGGUAUUCAAAAGUUGAUCUGACAUAAAGCCAAUCUGAUGGCUUAAAUUUCAUGAUGUCCUGGAAAAAUUGAGCUGAUGUUCUAAUCAUGUCAGAUAAAGAUGAUAUUGAGACUCCACUGCUAACUGAAGCAGCCCCCAUCCUUGAAGAUGGAAACUGUGAGCCAGCCAAGAAUUCUGAGUCUGUUGACCAAGGUGCCAAACCAGAGAGUAAAUCAGAACCUGUAGUUUCCACUCGGAAAAGACCAGAGACCAAACCUUCCAGUGACCUUGAGACUUCAAAAGUUCUCCCUAUUCAGGAUAAUGUUUCCAAAGAUGUACCCCAGACCAGAUGGGGUUAUUGGGGGAGCUGGGGCAAGUCCAUACUCUCCUCAGCCUCGGCUACAGUAGCUACAGUAGGACAAGGCAUUUCAAAUGUCAUCGAGAAGGCAGAGACUUCCCUUGGAAUCCCUGGUCCCAGUGAAAUUUCAACUGAAGUCAAGUAUGUAGCAGGAGAGACAAAUGCCAAAGAGAAUGAAAACUCCUCCCCAGUGGCUGGGGCAUUUGGUGUAUUCUCUACCAUCUCUACUGCUGUUCAGAGCACAGGAAAGAGUGUUAUAAGUGGGGGUUUGGAUGCCUUAGAAUUCAUUGGAAAAAAGACAAUGGAUGUGAUAGCAGAAGGGGAUCCUGGAUUUAAAAGAACCAAGGGUCUGAUGAACCGAAAUGCUACACUAUCUCAGGUUUUACGAGAGGCGAAGGAGAAAGAAGAGAUACGGACCUCCAAUGAGGUUACCGUGGAAACAGACAAGAAAACUCAUUAUGGGCUACUCUUUGAUGAAUUUCAAGGCCUUUCACAUCUAGAAGCUCUGGAGAUGCUUUCCCAAGAAAGUGAAAUAAAGGUGAAAUCUAUCCUUAAUUCUCUGAGUGGAGAAGAAUUAGAGACUCUAAAAGUUGAAUUAGAGCAACUCAAAGAAACAUUUUCUCUAGCAGAAUUUUGUGAAGAAGAGGAAGAAGAGAAAAAAGGGGAUGAAGAUUUUACCAAGGACAUAACAGAGCUGUUUUCCCAGCUGCACGUUUCCUCCAAACCAGAGAAACUUGCCAGGGCAAGAAAUACCGCCCACGAAUGGAUCAGGAAGUCUCUGACCAAGCCAUUAGCAGAGAAUGAAGAAGGAGAAAAACAGUCGGAAGCAGAAAAUACUGAGCAAGUCAACAAAAAUUCAAUAGAGGAUAUCCAUGCGUUUGCAAUCCGGAGCCUGGCUGAACUGACUGCCUGCUCAAUUGAACUAUUCCACAAAACAGCUGCAUUGGUUCUGCAUGGCAGGAAGCAGGAAGUGACAGCCAUAGAAAGGAGCCAAACUCUUUCCCAGAUGACAAUUGUGUUGUGUAAAGAGUUGUCCUCUCUGUCUAAAGAGUUCACUACCUGCCUAACAACUGCUGGGGUCAAAGAAAUGGCAGAUGUCCUUAACCCAUUAAUCACUGCAGUAUUUCUAGAGGCAUCAAACAGUGCCUCCUACAUCCAGGACGCCUUUCAGCUACUCUUACCUGUGCUAGAGAUCUCUCUCAUUGAGAACAAGAUUGAAUCACACAGACAUGAGCUGCAGGGCCAGAAACCUUUGUUAGAACAUUGAAGAAUGGAGACGUUUUGACCUGGGACUUGUGACGGCCAAGGAAUGCCACCUUAUUCUGGCUACUCCUGCAGAAAUGAAGGAGUGGGGUUAUUUUAGUAUAUAAAAAUUCAGGCAGGAGAGAUGGUUUAAAGAGGAAGAUUGUUGCCUUCAGUGUUUGAUUGAAGUAUUCAGGUUCUCACAGUAUUCUUUCCAGUUGUUGUAAUUCAUAAAUUAUUUGAAAAGAAACUUUUGUAGAAAGUCCAAGAAUAAUAACUCUAGAUAAAGAUUAGUGGGACACUCAGGCAAAAAUGUUGGUCUUUCUUUGACAUGUUGCAAAAUGUUAUCAAUUUUGUCAUGGAUAUAAUUUGCAGCCCAUGGAUAUAACUGGUUGAUAAGCCAGAGAAAAAUAAUUUAGUGUUCUAAAAUUCAUGGCAUGUGUGGUUUAUUAAUGCCAUGUACUUUCUCCUUUCUGGAAUAAAAUCUAUGGCUUUAAGAAAACUGAGCAUAUGUAAACUCUGUGAUGAUUACCCUUUAUCACAUGAAUUCUUGGAAAUAGAAAGUUUCAUCUGCUUUUUUAAAUUCUUAGUAGAUAUUUGGCAUUGAGGAGAAACUUGUAGACUAUUAUAGCCAUGUGAAUUAACUGUAGCAAAGUGCCCUUUUUCUUCAAAUUGCUCCCCCUCCCCAGGAUGACACACUUCAUGUCAUAGCUGAACCCUACUCUACUGGAUUCAAGGCCAGUAAAUGCAAUUUAGAGAAGCAGUUUUAUGUUUGCAGAUAUUCUGAGUCUCUUCAGGAUGUGUUUCGUGUCUACCAUAUAUGCAGGAUAAAUUCUUUAACAGCAAACUCCAAAGGAAUGUUGAAGCUGUUUUAGCAAUGAGGAUUUUUUUGUUUGAGUGUUGAAGUGGGCCAUAGUCCUUUAGAAAUGAUGUUCAUUUAUGAUAGGAUUUAACUUCUAAGGCAUAGUUUAUUUUUUCCUCUUUCCUUUUUGUUUGUUUUAAUGUAUUCUUUAGCAUGUUUUUGAUAUAACUUUUAUCCUCCAGAUCUUAAGCUUUCUUUUGCUCUCUUCAGCAAUUUAAGAGACUAUUAAGCUGUCGUCUUCCUAAAAGCUAUUUUGGUAUCCACUCUUUUUAAAAAAAUUCUCCAACUUUGUGGUUUUUUAAUGAUUAAGGUAAUUUGUUAGCUCUGCCCCUCAUCUUCUAAAACCUUUGUAAUAAAAUGUAUUAAUCAUGUUAUUUGAUCCUUUCAUUUACUUUUGUAAACACGAGCCCUAAUAUCUUACUUAGACCAAAAAAAAAAAAAAAAAAUAGCAAAGCAAAGCCAUAACAUAGAUUAGUAUAAAGACUGUUUCUACGUAAUCUUCUUUGGGGCAGGAGUCAGUUAGUAAGCAAGGAAGAGAAAUAAAUUUGGUUUAAAAAGGUAUACCAACAGCACUACAAUGUUACUCUGCCUAUAUUCUGUCUUAAUAUGAUCAGAAAGUUUUUGAAUAUUCCUUUUUAAAGACAAAUUUCACCCUUUCCAGCUUGAAUAUUUCUGAAGUUUCAGAAAAACAGUUGCCUUCUGGUUACAAAGGCUGGUGUCACCAGUUCUGAAUUGUUGCCUCAAGCUUGGUUGAUGUGUCUGAACCUGUAUCCCUUGAGGGCAAAGUUUAGAAACUGGUCACUCUGCCUACUGUCUGUUCAGCCUCUUGUACAAUGGCAGUUUGGCAGCUUUAAAUCCUUAACCUAGAAAUGUAUUUAAGGUUUUUCUUUCAAGAAAUGGGGUAUACAUAUGAAGGAGAGAGUAACAACUCUUUUUAUACACCUAUUCAGAUUUCAGCCCUGAAUUUGGCAAAUUUUAGAUUAGGUCUCACAUAAGGUAAAUAUGACUCACUAACUCUUUUUUUCUCAUCUUCCCCACCCCCCCAUAUAUAUUUAUUUAUUUUAAUGGAGUUAGGGACCACUAGUGAAAUGAUGAAAGGCCCAAUUCUGAGUAACAAUUGUCUACUCUUCACAUAAAAUAUACUGAAAAAGAAUUAAGAUUCCUUGAUCCAGUAGACAUAGAGAAACAUAAACAUUCAUGACAGAUGAGUAGGUAAAUUCAGGGAUCACUUUGGAACUUGCUGGAUUAUGGUGAUGGUUUUUGGAUAGUAUGUGCUUCAUUAUUUUAUUUGGGGUAGUUACAGUGUUUUAGUUUUUUGUUAACAGCUACACUUUUGGUACUAUUUUCCUUUUAAAUUUUUGGUGUCUAAGAUUUACCACUAAUUACUAAUAUAUGCCUUUCCAAUUCACUUAAAACCUUAAUAAGUGAAAUGUUCAGGUAUUGCUAGGGUAAAUGUGUCUUUUCCUACUAUUGAGAUUUUAAAAGGCUGUGAUUAAGAGAGACUUUAUUAAUUUGAUCUGAAAGAAGUAGAAACCUCUAUGAAACAAUUUUUAUUUUCCUUUGCAUAAUACCUUAGAAAUGUGUUAAGGACAAGCUAUAUUUUCCUUACUUGCUUUUGAUAGUUUUUUUUUUUUUUUUUAAGCAUAGAUAUCCAGGUUGGCAGGCCUCUGAAAUGUGAAAUUGUAAUUUUUAUAGAUGGCAUUACUAUGAAUCUGAAAUCAGUGCUAGGUGUACAAAUGUGAAUUUUUCAAUCCUGUAAUCAAAGAACAAGAUCUUGUGGGUUCCUACUGCUGAAAAAGGAUGCUUUCUUUUGUACUUGUUUUUAGUGAAAGACCUUUUUGAGGGAGAGCUAUUUUAUAGGUAGUUGCUAUUGAUAUCUCCAUUUGAGAAAUAGACAUUUUUCUGUAUUUCUAGAGGUGUUCUGAAUUUUAAACCUGAAUUCUUCAGUUUAGAAAACCCAGAAUAAAAUUAUACCCACAGUGGGCACUCAA